AGUGACUAGCUCCCGCGGCUAGCGGCACUGUCCACCGACGAGCGGCGCCCUCUUCUCCCCCUUCUCCCCACGAUUUCCUUCUCUGCGGCGGCACGCCGUCCAGCAGCCUGCUUCGCCCCGUCGUCAACUUUGAGCUGGAGGAGAAGCAACUUUGGCAGUGGCCGCGGGGUUGGAAUCCCGCUUCUCCUCGGCAGCAGUAGGCUCGCAAGUCGCUGGGGUUAGGUGGGGCAAGAGUUUCGCCGGCGCAUCAGCGCUGCUUCGGACUGUUUGCAACGUGUUUCCAGCGAGCUGGGAGCGGGGUUGUGACUGCGAGUCGUCUGGGGGAGGGGGACUUGUUUUUCUUUUCCUCUAGAGACCUCGGCUUGCAACUGGAUCAAACGCUGUCGAAAGGAUGUAAAUAGGCAGAGCAACUGUUACCAAGAAGGCCACCACCCCCACCCAAAGGCAGUGAGGAGUGUGGGGCUUCGUCUGGGCUCCCCCGAGUCUCAACAGUAAUCAACAGUCAGGUGUUGAUUGCAACUUUUCAAGGUCAGCCACCGGGAGUAGCCUAUUCCCUCUAGGAACCUUGGAGGGCAUACCUUGCUGGGACUCAACUUGGCUGAGAAAUGCACAAGAUGCCAAAGGAGGAAGGAUUAUAGGGGGCGUGUGUGUGACCCCCAAGACCGAUCUUCCGCUAUCACCCUAAUCUCCGGUUCCCCGCUACCCGGGCGGGGGUGAGUAUGUGACAUGUGCCUAACUCUCAGCAGCAACUUCGGCAGCAGGUGUCGAUCCUAACUAAGCAGGAGCUGCGGCUGCCGGGUGUGCCCUCACCAAGCCAUGCGAGCCCCGGGCGCGCUUCUCGCCCGCAUGUCGCGGCUACUGCUUCUGCUACUGCUCAAGGUGUCUGCCUCUUCUGCCCUCGGGGUCGCCCCUGCGUCCAGAAACGAAACUUGUCUGGGGGAGAGCUGUGCACCUACAGUGAUCCAGCGCCGCGGCAGGGACGCCUGGGGACCGGGAAAUUCUGCAAGAGACGUUCUGCGAGCCCGAGCACCCAGGGAGGAGCAGGGGGCAGCGUUUCUUGCGGGACCCUCCUGGGACCUGCCGGCGGCCCCGGGCCGUGACCCGGCUGCAGGCAGAGGGGCGGAGGCGUCGGCAGCCGGACCCCCGGGACCUCCAACCAGGCCACCUGGCCCCUGGAGGUGGAAAGGUGCUCGGGGUCAGGAGCCUUCUGAAACUUUGGGGAGAGGGAACCCCACGGCCCUCCAGCUCUUCCUUCAGAUCUCAGAGGAGGAAGAGAAGGGUCCCAGAGGCGCUGGCAUUUCCGGGCGUAGCCAGGAGCAGAGUGUGAAGACAGUCCCCGGAGCCAGCGAUCUUUUUUACUGGCCAAGGAGAGCCGGGAAACUCCAGGGUUCCCACCACAAGCCCCUGUCCAAGACGGCCAAUGGACUGGCGGGGCACGAAGGGUGGACAAUUGCACUCCCGGGCCGGGCGCUGGCCCAGAAUGGAUCCUUGGGUGAAGGAAUCCAUGAGCCUGGGGGUCCCCGCCGGGGAAACAGCACGAACCGGCGUGUGAGACUGAAGAACCCCUUCUACCCGCUGACCCAGGAGUCCUAUGGAGCCUACGCGGUCAUGUGUCUGUCCGUGGUGAUCUUCGGGACCGGCAUCAUUGGCAACCUGGCGGUGAUGUGCAUCGUGUGCCACAACUACUACAUGCGGAGCAUCUCCAACUCCCUCUUGGCCAACCUGGCCUUCUGGGACUUUCUCAUCAUCUUCUUCUGCCUUCCGCUGGUCAUCUUCCACGAGCUGACCAAGAAGUGGCUGCUGGAGGACUUCUCCUGCAAGAUCGUGCCCUAUAUAGAGGUCGCUUCUCUGGGAGUCACCACUUUCACCUUAUGUGCUCUGUGCAUAGACCGCUUCCGUGCUGCCACCAACGUACAGAUGUACUACGAAAUGAUCGAAAACUGUUCCUCAACAACUGCCAAACUUGCUGUUAUAUGGGUGGGAGCUCUAUUGUUAGCACUUCCAGAAGUUGUUCUCCGCCAGCUGAGCAAGGAGGAUUUGGGGUUUAGUGGCCGAGCUCCGGCAGAAAGGUGCAUUAUUAAGAUCUCUCCUGAUUUACCAGACACCAUCUAUGUUCUAGCCCUCACCUACGACAGUGCGAGACUGUGGUGGUAUUUUGGCUGUUACUUUUGUUUGCCCACGCUUUUCACCAUCACCUGCUCUCUAGUGACUGCGAGGAAAAUCCGCAAAGCAGAGAAAGCCUGUACCCGAGGGAAUAAACGGCAGAUUCAACUAGAGAGUCAGAUGAACUGUACAGUAGUGGCACUGACCAUUUUAUAUGGAUUUUGCAUUAUUCCUGAAAAUAUCUGCAACAUUGUUACUGCCUACAUGGCUACAGGGGUUUCACAGCAGACAAUGGACCUCCUUAAUAUCAUCAGCCAGUUCCUUUUGUUCUUUAAGUCCUGUGUCACCCCAGUCCUCCUUUUCUGUCUCUGCAAACCCUUCAGUCGGGCCUUCAUGGAGUGCUGCUGCUGUUGCUGUGAGGAAUGCAUUCAGAAGUCUUCAACGGUGACCAGUGAUGACAAUGACAACGAGUACACCACGGAACUCGAACUCUCGCCUUUCAGUACCAUACGCCGUGAAAUGUCCACUUUUGCUUCUGUCGGAACUCAUUGCUGAAGGACAGUACUUGGUUGGGUCAGAUUUAUUUGUUUGAUUUUCAUAUCCCGUGAAAGUUUUUAAUUCAUAUUUUUCCUUAUAGGGAAAAAUGCAAAAAAGAAACAAUAAAGAAAGAAAUAUUAACUACUGUAGAACUGAUUUUACAAAUUAAUAUUUGUGCUUUGAAAAAAAGUUUCUAUUUAGUUAUUUAAGAAGAAUGAGAAGGCCAAUAGUUUUAGAUUAUUUUAUCUGGUAUGGUGCUAAUAUUUUAUUUGAAAAAAGUUACUGCAACUUAACUUAAAAUUGCUAACGUUUUUUCUUCUUUUAAAAAUACAAUUAUUGUAUAUUGAUUAUAGCAAUGUGAUUUUGUAGGUUAUUUUAUAUUUGAGUUGUGAUUGAAAGUAUGUUGUAUAUGGUAUUGUGAGAUGAUUUGUACUUGGAAGCAUUCACAAAGUAGCACCAAAUAAAUUACACUUUAUUCUUUAAUGUCAUUGUCAAUCUACUUUUAACCAAUAUUCAAUAAAUCUUCUAAUUGCCUUAAAGAUACAAUUACUGGUUCUAUGCACAAUUUAAAACCGGCCUUACUGUUUUAUAACGUAUUUUCUUUUAAGGCAGGUAAUCAUUAUGUUAUAAAGAAGUUUUUCUAAUAGCAGUAUUUUAUAUGCAUGAUUCAUAAAACUAUGUUGUAUGUUAAAACAAAGCUGUAUUUUUAAUAUUCAGGUAUAGAUGUCAAAUUACUUCUGAAUACUUAUAAAAUAUGAAUAAAUAGCAGAGUAGGAAGAAAGUUUCUUUUUUAAAAAAUUCACCUCUGAACUAGCACAUAGAGCUACAGAUUUUCCCUUGGGGAAUUAUGGGCAGAAUCAAGAAUUUUAAAAUGCAGUUGUCAUCUGAUUUCCUCUGAACACUGACCUUUGAAGCUUUGUGAAUCCUACGUAAAGCACUCUGAGUUCUAAUUUUUCUCCUUUUGAAAAAUAAACUUGAUGAAAUCUAUACAACUUAAUUUCUUUAAGUGCAAUGAAAGUAUAGGAGUGGAAUAAUAAAAUAUUUAUAUAUUUUUAUUAGAACAUUCUACCUUUAACUUGAUACUUCAUAAACUCUGAAUAAAAAAACCUAACCUCCUCCAUUGGGAAUAUUUGAAUCCCCUCUUUUGCCUCUUCUGGAGUUUAAAAUGCAGCAGUUGUGUAGGAUGCUUGCUGUGUGGGACACAUGUCUAACUCAGGUGGCAGAGACCAUGACCUAGUGACACAGUGAUAUUUAAAAGCUACCAAAGAAGAUGUGUAGUUGGAUGUCUUUGUCUUCAGAAAAAUCUUGUUAUAGAGAACCCAGUUUUCUUGCUGGGAAAACGUAGUUUCUGCUUGUUGAUUUCUGUUCUACUCGGCAUAAGUAAGUCAGUAUUCCUUUUUCCAAAUUAUAACAUGAUGUUAUUUAAAAAUCAUUAAAGAGAUUGGUGCAGGUGAAACUUAAAUGGCAGUGCCCAGGCUAUCUCCUUUUUCCCAGUCCAAUACUUUUCAAAGGGGUUUUUCCCUCCAUUGUGUGUAUUCUGUGGGAUCUGCAGGAGAAUUCAAACAAGGUGCCCUUGUCUUCUUGUAGAUCCCUGUAAUAGGUCUUUGGAAAAUUUCUCAAGAGGACACCUGAGCUAGGUUUUGGCUGCUGAGCAGAACAGCAACUGUGAUUCCAUAGUGUCUCUCCUGAUAUUUAGUCACUUUAUAAAUCAAGGAACAAUUGAGCAUGUCAUGUGGAAAAGAUUCUAUCCUAUUACCUGAGUAACUAAAGGUAAAUAGGUCACAGCCUCAGACCUUACAGAAUCAGGCAGGGAUGACAUGGAUGGGAAGGAAUAAAAUAAAUACAUAGACAACUAUGAUAUAAGCUGGGGCUUGUUAGGUGCCUCAGGAAGAUGUGAAGUUCUGCGAUACUUUGGAAUAGAGGGAAUGCUUAUAGGGUUAGAAGAGAGCAUGAAAGGCUUUAUGAGAUAACUGGAUGAGUGGGCUUUUAGAAGGAGCUGAUGAAAGAUGGUGUGAGGAGUGGACACUUCAGGAGGAGAGAGCUAAUUUAUAAAGGAAUAGAAGAAGAAAUCAGUGGGUGUGAUUGAAGAAUAAACAGCCCAGUUUGACUUCUGUGCUACGUGUGCAUAGCAGCCUUGUGGGAAAUAUUAAAGAAAAUAUGCACCAAGGCCAUCUAAUAAUAGGACCAUGUUUUGAAAGAUGUUUACAUGGUGGUGCUUCAGGAAAUGGGGCUUUGCUUUUAAGGUUUUUGAGUAUGGAGAAAUAGUAUCCCAGCUCUGCAAUAGGAAGAUCAACUUGCAAACAGUUUAAAUAGGCUGGUAGGGGACAGUCUGAUCAUGAAAAAGCAACUAGGAAGCUAUUAUAAGAGAUUGAACCACAAUGGAGGCAGCAGGAACUUAAAUUUCUUUUUUCAUUUAUACUUGCCUUUCAACUUUUUGUAGUUGCAACAUGUACUUUCUUAUUGAAUCCUACCUCUGUCAAAGUGGAAACUUUGAUAACUCAAAUUGUCCCAAGUAUAAAGUGAUUUCAAAGUUUUCUCAUAGUCGUCUUGUGUUUUUCACAAAAACCAAUUUCUAUAAUAUACUUUUAAAAAAUUGUUAAUCAUUUCUGUUCAACAUUUCUUCAGUCUGGAUCUUAUCCAAUGUCUUACGCUCCUCGU